GCACUUAAGGAGCUCGGGCCAGCGCGAGGGGGAGCAGGGAGGAAGCCCGGCUGCUGCGGACCUCCUCGGACCCGGACCCAGCCCCAGCCCGGCCCCAGCCAGCCCCGACGGCGCCAUGCGGGGUCCGAGCGGGGCUCUGUGGCUGCUCCUGGCUCUGCGCACCGUGCUCGGUGGCAUGGAGGUGCGGUGGUGCGCCACCUCGGACCCAGAGCAGCACAAGUGCGGCAACAUGAGCGAGGCCUUCCGGGAAGCGGGCAUCCAGCCCUCCCUCCUCUGCGUCCGGGGCACCUCCGCCGACCACUGCGUCCAGCUCAUCGCGGCCCAGGAGGCUGACGCCAUCACUCUGGAUGGAGGAGCCAUCUAUGAGGCGGGAAAGGAGCACGGCCUGAAGCCGGUGGUGGGCGAAGUGUACGAUCAAGAGGUCGGUACCUCCUAUUACGCCGUGGCUGUGGUCAGGAGGAGCUCCCAUGUGACCAUUGACACCCUGAAAGGCGUGAAGUCCUGCCACACGGGCAUCAAUCGCACAGUGGGCUGGAACGUGCCCGUGGGCUACCUGGUGGAGAGCGGCCGCCUCUCGGUGAUGGGCUGCGAUGUACUCAAAGCUGUCAGCGACUAUUUUGGGGGCAGCUGCGUCCCGGGGGCAGGAGAGACCAGUUACUCUGAGUCCCUCUGUCGCCUCUGCAGGGGUGACAGCUCUGGGGAAGGGGUGUGUGACAAGAGCCCCCUGGAGAGAUACUACGACUACAGCGGGGCCUUCCGGUGCCUGGCGGAAGGGGCAGGGGACGUGGCUUUUGUGAAGCACAGCACGGUACUGGAGAACACGGAUGGGAAGACGCUUCCCUCCUGGGGCCAGGCCCUGCUGUCACAGGACUUCGAGCUGCUGUGCCGGGAUGGUAGCCGGGCCGAUGUCACCGAGUGGAGGCAGUGCCAUCUGGCCCGGGUGCCUGCUCACGCCGUGGUGGUCCGGGCCGACACAGAUGGGGGCCUCAUCUUCCGGCUGCUCAACGAAGGCCAGCGUCUGUUCAGCCACGAGGGCAGCAGCUUCCAGAUGUUCAGCUCUGAGGCCUAUGGCCAGAAGGAUCUACUCUUCAAAGACUCUACCUCGGAGCUUGUGCCCAUCGCCACACAGACCUAUGAGGCGUGGCUGGGCCAUGAGUACCUGCACGCCAUGAAGGGUCUGCUCUGUGACCCCAACCGGCUGCCCCCCUACCUGCGCUGGUGUGUGCUCUCCACUCCCGAGAUCCAGAAGUGUGGAGACAUGGCCGUGGCCUUCCGCCGGCAGCGGCUCAAGCCAGAGAUCCAGUGCGUGUCAGCCAAGUCCCCCCAACACUGCAUGGAGCGGAUCCAGGCUGAGCAGGUCGACGCUGUGACCCUGAGUGGCGAGGACAUUUACACGGCGGGGAAGACGUACGGCCUGGUUCCCGCAGCCGGGGAGCACUAUGCCCCGGAAGACAGCAGCAACUCGUACUACGUGGUGGCCGUGGUGAGACGGGACAGCUCCCACGCCUUCACCUUGGAUGAGCUUCGGGGCAAGCGCUCCUGCCACGCCGGUUUCGGCAGCCCUGCAGGCUGGGAUGUCCCCGUGGGUGCCCUUAUUCAGAGAGGCUUCAUCCGGCCCAAGGACUGUGACGUCCUCACAGCAGUGAGCGAGUUCUUCAAUGCCAGCUGCGUGCCCGUGAACAACCCCAAGAACUACCCCUCCUCGCUGUGUGCACUGUGCGUGGGGGACGAGCAGGGCCGCAACAAGUGUGUGGGCAACAGCCAGGAGCGGUAUUACGGCUACCGCGGCGCCUUCAGGUGCCUGGUGGAGAAUGCGGGUGACGUUGCCUUCGUCAGGCACACAACCGUCUUUGACAACACAAACGGCCACAAUUCCGAGCCCUGGGCUGCUGAGCUCAGGUCAGAGGACUAUGAACUGCUGUGCCCCAACGGGGCCCGAGCCGAGGUGUCCCAGUUUGCAGCCUGCAACCUGGCACAGAUACCACCCCACGCCGUGAUGGUCCGGCCCGACACCAACAUCUUCACCGUGUAUGGACUGCUGGACAAGGCCCAGCAAUUUGCAGCUAGCGGCACUGGGCGGGUGACCCUGCCUGAGCCCAGUGAGGAGCAGGUCGUCUGCCUGCGGUGCUUCCAGGACCUGUUUGGAGACGACCACAAUAAGAACGGGUUCAAAAUGUUCGACUCCUCCAACUAUCAUGGCCAAGACCUGCUUUUCAAGGAUGCCACCGUCCGGGCGGUGCCUGUCGGAGAGAAAACCACCUACCGCGGCUGGCUGGGGCUGGACUACGUGGCGGCGCUGGAAGGGAUGUCGUCUCAGCAGUGCUCGGGCGCAGCGGCCCCGGCGCCCGGGGCGCCCCUGCUCCCGCUGCUGCUGCCCGCCCUCGCCGCCCGCCUGCUCCCGCCCGCCCUCUGAGCCCGGCCGCCCCGCCCCAGAGCUCCGAUGCCCGCCCGGGGAGUUUCCGCGGCGGCUUCGCGCUGGAAUCCAGAAGGAAGCUCGCGAAGGCCGGGCCCGGCGUGGGCGGGAGCAGGCGCCUCCCCGGGAGCCCCGCCGCCCACGGGCGCCACCUGGCGCUGCUACCUGAGGCGCCGCCCCCGGGCCCGCGCGGCCCUUCCCGCCAACCGCCGCCUCCCGCCACCUGGAGCCGCGCGGGCCGCGCCGGAGGAGGCCGGUUGCCCAGGAAACCGCUGAGUCCGGGCUUCCCGCCGCCCGCCCCGCGGUGUCGCCCGAGGGGCCCGCCCGCCUCCUCCCCGCAGCCCCGCGCCCCCGUCCGCGAGGCCCCCUGGGGACGCGGUGGCCGCCGAGGCGCCUACACCCGCAGGCCGCGGCCAGGCCGUCCCAGGAGGCCCCGGCGCCAACGGGACCCGGCGCGUGGGACAGCGGCCUCUGCUGGCGGCGGCGGGAGGGAGGCCGGACCGGGGCGACGGGGAGAAGCCUUCGCCCGCGGGACCGUGUCCGGGGUGGGGGCUCCAGUUCCUCCGACCGCCCGUGCGCUGGGAGGGAGGCCGAGCCCGGGGAACGCCGCGUGCCCUGCCUCGUCCCCCACUGUGGCCGCGCCAGCUCCAUCCCGGGCCAGCCGCGUCCACGGGCCCCCUCCCGAGUCUCCUCAGGCUCUCGCCUCCCCUACCCCCGUGGGAUGCCCACCGCCCGCACCCACGCCCGAGCCUGGCGGCAGCAGCCGCCCCCCGCCUGAAGGGAGCCGGAGGUGACCCAGGCCGCGGGCUCCCGAGGCCCCUGAAGGGCUGCGCGUGGGGACCCGCCAUGCUUCUGGGUUCCGAACGGGGGUGAGCUCCGUCUCCUCACCCGGCCCCGCACCCGCUGGGCCUGGGGACCCCUCACUCCCCGUGCCCGCCCCUCCGCGAGGCAGCAGAAAGCGCCCGGCCGGGGCCUCUCUCUACUCCAUCUUGCCACAGUUGUCUGAGAAGCCAGAAAAAGUUUCCAGAACUGGCAGCCCUUAAAAAAAAUGAAGAGGAAGAGAAGAAAUGGGAGCAGGCAGCCCUCGUCAGCAGACCGGGAGCCGCGUGGGCGCGGAGCCAUUUGCAUUCCGGUCUGCGGGGGCUCGGGGAUGCUGGUGACAGGCCCGGUUCCCGGUGGCUCGCCCCCACCUGCGGGCGUCGGGAAGGAUCCCUUCCAUCUCUCAGCCGCAGAGGAGGCCCUGGCAGCGCCCCGGCUGUAGCCAUGCAACCCCGAGGAGUCCCGGGCACCUUCACCCCACCGGGAGGGGCCACAAGGACCUGGGCCUCGGCCACCAAGCUUUGUCCCCUCUCGCUGUGGGGGGCUAGUGAUUCUCCUCCGACCUGACGAUUGCUUGGUUUUUUCAAAAGGGAGUUUUGUGCGGUGAGAAGUGUGUUUCUGUGUGGCUAACUCUGGGCUAGCGUGCCGUGGCCAUUGAAGGUGUGGCCUGCGUGGGUGCAGUGUAAGUGACGCUGGAUUGUCAGGUGGCAGCAGGGGACCCCUGCUGUGUCAGUGCUAAUGAAACAUGUUGGUUGGUUUCUAAAAUAAAGCCAAACAAGCCAGCACAUGCAGAGGCUUGGACCCUGAUAGAAA